AGCCCUCCAGGACAGGCUGCAUCAGAAGAGGCCAUCAAGCAGGUCUGUUCCAAGGGCCUUUGCGUCAGGUGGGCUCAGGAUUCCAGGGUGGCUGGACCCCAGGCCCCAGCUCUGCAGCAGGGAGGACGUGGCUGGGCUCGUGAAGCAUGUGGGGGUGAGCCCAGGGGCCCCAAGGCAGGGCACCUGGCCUUCAGCCUGCCUCAGCCCUGCCUGUCUCCCAGAUCACUGUCCUUCUGCCAUGGCCCUGUGGAUGCGCCUCCUGCCCCUGCUGGCGCUGCUGGCCCUCUGGGGACCUGACCCAGCCGCAGCCUUUGUGAACCAACACCUGUGCGGCUCACACCUGGUGGAAGCUCUCUACCUAGUGUGCGGGGAACGAGGCUUCUUCUACACACCCAAGACCCGCCGGGAGGCAGAGGACCUGCAGGUGGGGCAGGUGGAGCUGGGCGGGGGCCCUGGUGCAGGCAGCCUGCAGCCCUUGGCCCUGGAGGGGUCCCUGCAGAAGCGUGGCAUUGUGGAACAAUGCUGUACCAGCAUCUGCUCCCUCUACCAGCUGGAGAACUACUGCAACUAGACGCAGCCCGCAGGCAGCCCCACACCCGCCGCCUCCUGCACCGAGAGAGAUGGAAUAAAGCCCUUGAACCAGC